AGAAAGCAUCCAACCCACUGAAAAGACAGGCAUUAAAGGAGCUUCGCCUACAGAGCUGCUGGAGGAUACACUCUCCAGGGGGUUCCUGUUAAAAACCAGAGCUUCAGCUUCCAAAAUUACGGCUGAGCUUCAGUUUUUCCACAAGAGAUUGCCUAAAGGAACCAUGGAGAUCAGAGGGGCACUCGAUCUGCGAAAAAGGCAAGUUCUAAUAUUCCUUGUUUUGCUGGGAUUGUCUCGGGCAGGUACUGAAUCUGCACACUAUUCUGUGGCAGAGGAAACAGAAAUUGGCUCUUUUGUGGCUAAUCUAGCGAGGGACCUAGGGCUGGGGGUGGAGGAGCUGUCUUCACGUGAAGCCCGGGUAGUGUCUGAUGAUAAUAAAAAGUAUUUGCACCUUGAUUUGCUGACUGGGAAUUUGCUCCUAAAUGAGAAACUAGACCGAGACGAGCUGUGUGGCUCCACCGAGCCCUGUGUGCUGCAUUUUCAGGUGGUUUUGGAAAACCCUUUACAGUUUUUUCGGUUUGAGCUGUGUGUCAAAGACAUAAAUGAUCACUCCCCUACAUUUCUAGACAAGGAAAUACUUAUUAAAAUAUCAGAAGGUACCACUGUUGGAGCUACCUUUCUAAUGGAGAGUGCUCAAGAUUUGGAUGUCGGAAGCAACAGUCUCCAAAACUACACAAUUAGCCCCAAUUCUCACUUCUACAUUAAAAUUCCCGACAGUAGUGACAGAAAGAUAUACCCAGAGCUGGUCCUAGAUAGAGCUUUAGAUUAUGAACAGGAAGCUGAACUCAGAUUAACACUCACAGCAGUGGAUGGUGGAUCCCCGCCCAAGUCUGGGACAACUUUGGUUCUCAUCAAGGUGUUGGACAUCAAUGAUAAUGCCCCUGAGUUUCCUCAGAGUCUCUAUGAGGUGCAAGUCCCCGAGGACAGACCCCUUGGCUCCUGGAUUGCCACCAUCUCAGCUAAGGAUCUGGAUGCAGGAAACUAUGGAAAAAUAUCUUACACAUUUUUCCAUGCAUCAGAAGAUAUUCGUAAAACAUUUGAAAUUAAUCCAAUAUCUGGGGAAGUUAAUUUGAGAUCACCCCUGGAUUUUGAAGUAAUACAGUCCUACACUAUAAAUAUUCAGGCAACAGAUGGUGGGGGUCUUUCAGGAAAAUGCACCCUUCUAGUUAAAGUUAUGGAUAUAAACGACAACCCACCAGAAGUGACCAUAUCGUCGAUUACAAAGAGAAUUCCAGAGAAUGCCUCAGAGACCCUAGUAGCUCUUUUUAGUAUCCUAGACCAAGACUCUGGAGACAAUGGGAGGAUGAUUUGCUCUAUUCAAGAUAACCUCCCUUUUUUCCUGAAACCGACCUUCAAGAACUUUUUCACUCUAGUUUCUGAAAAAGCACUGGACAGAGAGAGCCAAGCCGAGUACAACAUCACGAUCACCGUCACAGACUUGGGGACACCCAGGCUGAAAACCGAGUACAACAUAACCGUGCUGCUCUCUGACGUCAAUGACAACGCCCCCACCUUCACCCAAACCUCCUACACCCUGUUCGUCCGCGAGAACAACAGCCCCGCCCUGCACAUCGGCAGCGUCAGCGCCACAGACAGAGACUCAGGCACCAACGCCCAGGUCAACUACUCGCUGCUGCCGCCCCAGGACCGGCACCUGCCCCUCGCCUCCUUGGUCUCCAUCAACGCGGACAAUGGCCACCUGUUUGCCCUCAGGUCGCUGGACUACGAGGCCCUACAGGAGUUCGAGUUUCGCGUGGGCGCCACAGACCGCGGGUCCCCGGCGUUGAGCAGCGAGGCGCUGGUGCGCGUGCUGGUGCUGGACGCCAACGACAACUCGCCCUUCGUGCUGUACCCGCUGCAGAACGGCUCCGCGCCCUGCACCGAGCUGGUGCCCCGGGCGGCCGAGCCGGGCUACCUGGUGACCAAGGUGGUGGCGGUGGACGGCGACUCGGGCCAGAACGCCUGGCUGUCGUACCAGCUGCUCAAGGCCACGGAGCCCGGGCUGUUCGGCGUGUGGGCGCACAAUGGCGAGGUGCGCACCGCCAGGCUGCUGAGCGAGCGCGACGCGGCCAAGCACAGGCUGGUGGUGCUGGUCAAGGACAAUGGCGAGCCUCCUCGCUCGGCCACCGCCACGCUGCACGUGCUCCUGGUGGACGGCUUCUCCCAGCCCUACCUGCCGCUCCCUGAGGCGGCCCCGGCCCAGGCCCAGGCCGACUCCCUCACCGUCUACCUGGUGGUGGCAUUGGCCUCGGUGUCGUCGCUCUUCCUCUUCUCGGUGCUCCUGUUCGUGGCGGUGCGGCUGUGCAGGAGGAGCAGGGCGGCCUCGGUGGGUCGCUGCUCGGUGCCCGAGGGUCCCUUUCCAGGGCAUCUGGUGGACGUGAGCGGCACCGGGACCCUGUCCCAGAGCUACCAAUACGAGGUGUGUCUGACAGGAGGUUCCGGGACAAAUGAGUUCAAAUUUCUGAAGCCGAUUAUCCCCAAUUUUCAAGUUCAUGACACUGGUAGGAAUAUGGGGGAAAUCGAGAACUUUCGAAAUAGCUUUGGACUUAACAUUCAAUAAAACAAUUUAUUUUAAAUGUCUAAUUUUUGGUUAUUCUUGGCAAGCUGAUGGUACUUUUUGCAUAAUCUUUUGUGGAUUCUUGGUUGUACUGUAGUUGCAUGCAUGAUUAUAGCUCUUGUUUUUCUCACAGUUUCUUUAAAAAUCUUUAUUAGUGGCUAUAAUGACGUGGAAAUGUAAUCUGUGUUUUCUGGUUUUUCAUUUAUUUGGCCAAAAUGUUAUAUUAAUGGAGUUAUUGCUAUUUUUGCUGUGAUAAUGGUAUUAUGCAAGACCAUAUUCUCAAUUAUUUGGAUAUGCAAACUAAAGUAUUAAGAGCUAAUGUCAUUAUAUAUGUAACUUAAAUCUAGACACCAUCAAAGCAUAAAAUAAAAAUAAAAAGCGUUGCUGAAUCUGGGUCGAAAAUGUAGUGCGUUUAUCCCACUAUUCUCUCUGAAAAUGUUCUUUAGAAAGGGUAACAAAGAUGCUAUCCCUCCAUUUUCAGUUCUGGAGAACCUUAUUAGUUUUUCAAAUAUUUACUUUAUGAUGAAACUUAAGUGGUCACAUUGGAAAUUAUUAAUUUCUUAAGUAAUUUUUUCUGUAACUGCUUUUGUUGAUAAUCCUGUUGUGGAGGAAGAGUCUUAUAAUGCUCUGGGCUUUGCUGUCACUCUUUGGUUUUCUUAAUUUAAUUCUAUUUAUUUAUGUUUUUUGAGACAGGGUCUCAUUCCAUUGACCUGGCUGGAAUGCAGUGGCACCAUCAUGGCUCACUGCCGCCUUGACUUCCUGGGUUCAGGUGAUUCUCCUGCCUCAGCCUCCUGAGUAGCUGGAUCACCAGCACAGGCCACUACGGCCUGGCUAAUUCUUUUGUAUUUUUUUUGUACAGAUGGAAUCUUGCCAUGUUUCCCAGUCUGGUCUGGAACUCCUUGGCUCAAGCGAUCUGCCCGCCUUAGCUAGUUUUUUGUUUUUGUUUUUUGAGACAAAGUCUCACUUUGUUGUCCAGGCUAGAGAGUAGUGGCAGGAUCUUGGCUCACUGCAGCCUCGACAUCCUGGGCUCAGGCAAUCCUCCUGCUUCGGCCUAUUAAAUAGCUCAAACUACAGGCACCCGCCACGAUGCCUAGCUAAAUUUUUGUAUAUGUGGUAGAGAUGGAGUUUUGCCAUGUGGCCCAGGCUAGUCUCGAACUCCUGAACUCAAGUGAUCCACCUGCUUUGGCCUCCCAACGUGCUAGGAUUACAGGCAUGAGCCAUUACGUCUGGCCUAGUUUUCUUUAAAUACACCGUGUUUACUAGCUUAAAUUUUGUGUUGUUUAUUACUAAAGCAGAAAAUAAUUUAGGGUCUUAUCCUGGGUAAAAUAGCCUUCCAUCAGAUGAGUACAAAGCAAGAACUUCAUAAGAAAUUGAAAUGAAGAUUCAAACUGUUAAAGAAAUGAUUUAGUUUCACUUUCCUAUUAAUUAUUGAGUAAAUAUAAAACAUCAUUAACACUUUGUGGCCUCUCUCAGAUGCCUACAAAGAAGGAAUGGGUAGGCAUUUAUGGUUUAUAGUUGCCUCAUCAUGUAACAUAUUAUAUCUCAGCUCUAAAAGAAAGUUCUAUAGAAGAUUAUAGAUAGAGAUUUUGAUAACUGGAAUGUAGUAUGGAUAUAGGGCUGGUGUACAUAUACAUUUUGAAAUUGCUCUUACAAGAUUAAAUACUAUUAUAGACCAGAUGAUGUAGUAAAAUGGAAUUUCACUUGCCAUUGUGAAAUAGGUGAAACAAAUUCCAGUUUCCUUAGAUUUCUUCCCUCUACUUUAUGCAAUUAUCACUGAUUUUAUUUUUCGUUGUAACAAGUAGUUAUUUGUUGUGUGGAUUUCUUAAAAUUGACAUUUAAACAAUAAAAUCCUGAAAAGAA